CGCCUCCUCUGGCUCAGUCACACAGCGACGUAGAGGUGACUGGAGGUAUAUACUUGUCCUCACCUGGAUCAUGCUGAUGUGGCCCCAACCCCACCUCCCUACCCAUCCCCACCUCCCUACCCAUCCCCACCUCCCUACCCAUCCCCACCUCCCUACCCAUCCCCACCUCCCUACCCAUCCUAUGAUGUCCAAAGAAACCAGACAGAGCAAAUUGGCCGAGGCCAAGGAACAGUUGACAGACCAUCAUCCCCAGACCAACCCUAGUGUUGGUACAGCAGCAAGCGACACCAAAAAGAAGAAAAUAAAUAAUGGCACUAACCCUGAGACAACCACUUCUGGUGGUUGCCACUCGCCUGAGGAUGAACAGAAGGCAAGCCACCAACAUCAGGAAGCCCUAAGGAGGGAGCUAGAGGCCCAGGUUCAUACCAUACGAAUCCUUACAUGUCAGAAAACUGAGCUUCAGAUGGCACUCUACUACAGCCAGCAUGCUGUCAAGCAGUUGGAAGGAGAGGCCAGGGAUCUGAUCAGCCGCCUGCAUGAUUCAUGGAAGUUUGCAGGAGAGUUAGAGCAGGCUCUCUCUGCUGUCGCUACACAGAAGAAGAAGGCGGAUAGGUACAUUGAGGAGUUAACAAAGGAGAGGGACGCCCUGAGUCUGGAACUGUACAGGAACACCAUAACUGAUGAGGAGCUGAAGGAGAAAAAUGCCAAACUACAAGAAAAACUUCAACUUGUAGAAUCUGAAAAGUCUGAGAUCCAGCUCAACGUAAAGGAGCUAAAAAGGAAACUGGAGAGGGCCAAGCUCCUGCUGCCACAGCAGCAGCUGCAGGCGGAGGCUGACCACCUGGGUAAGGAGCUGCAGAGUGUGUCAGCAAAGCUCCAAGCCCAGGUGGAAGAGAACGAGUUGUGGAACCGCCUGAACCAGCAACAGGAGGAGAAGAUGUGGAGGCAGGAGGAGAAGAUACAGGAGUGGGAGGAGAAGAUACAGGAGCAGGAGGAGAAGAUACGGGAGCAGGAGGAGAAGAUACGGGAGCAGGAGGAGAAGAUGCGGAGGCAGGAGGAGAUGAUGUGGGAGAAGGAGGAGAAGAUGCGGAGGCAGGAGGAGAUGAUGUGGGAGAAGGAGGAGAAGAUGCGGAGGCUGGAGGAGAUGAUGUGGGAGAAGGAGGAGAAGAUACGGGAGCUGGAAGAGAAGAUGCACGAGCAGGAGAAGAUACGGGAGCAGGAAGAGAAGAGGCAGGAGGAGGAGAAGAUACGCGAGCAGGAGAAGAGGCAGGAGCAGGAGGCGAAGAUGUGGAGGCAGGAGGAGAAGAUACGGGAGCAGGAAGAGAAGAUACGGGAGCAGGAGAAAAAGAUGUGGAGGCAGGAGGAGAAGAUUCACGAGCAGGAGAAGAUACGGGAGGAGGAGAAGAGGCAGGAGCAGGAGGAGAUGUGGAGGCAGGAGGAGAAGAUAAGGGAGCAGGAGGAGAUAUGGAGGCAAAAGGAGAAGAUGCACGAGCAGGAGAAGAUACGGAAGCAGGAGGAGAAGGUGUGGAGGCAGGAGGAGAAGAUGCACGACCAGGAGGAGAAGAUACGGGAGCAGGAGGAGAAGAUGUGGAGGCAGGAGGAGAAGAUAAGGGAGCAGGAGGAGAAGAUACGGGAGCAGGAGGAGAAGAUACGGGAGCAGGAGGAGAAGAUACGAGAGCAGGAGGAGAUGAUGCAGGAACAGGAAGAGAAGAUGGGGGAGCAGGAAGAGAAGAUGCAAGAACAGGAGAAGAUGCGGAGGCAGGAGGAGAAGAUAAGGGAGCAGGAGGAGAAGAUACGGGAGCAGAAGGAGAAGAUACGAGAGCAGGAGGAGAAGAUAUGGGAGCAGGAGGAGAAGAUACGAGAGCAGGAGGAGAUGAUGCAGGAACAGGAAGAGAAGAUGUGGGAGCAGGAGGAGAAGAUGUGUGAGCAGGAAGAGAAGAUGCAAGAACAGGAGGAGAAGAUGCGGAGGCAGGAGGAGAAGAUGUGGGAGCAGGAAGUGAGGCUGCGGCAGCAGGAGGAGAAGAUGCAGGAACACUAGGAGCACCUGGAAGCUGCCAUCUAAUGAGCACAUGACAAGAAGGCAAAGACAAUAAACAUGUAAAAGCCGGCAGCAAGGCCUGGAGAAGAGUAAGCCGCCAUGUGACUGUUUAGAAUAUAGUCUGAGCACAAACCUGAAAAAAAAAUUUUAUUUAUUUUAAAUUGUGGCAAAAUACUGGCCAGGCAUGGUAGCUCACGCCUGUAAUCCUAGCAAUUUGGGAGGCCGAGGUAAAUGGAUGACCUGAGGUCAAGAGUUCAAGACCAGCCUGGCCAAUACAAAAAUUAGCCGGGCAUGGUGGCGCAUGCCUGUAAUCCCAGCUACUUGGGAGGCUGAGGCAGGAGAAUCGCUUGAACCUGGGAGGCAGAGGUUGCAGUGAGCUGAGAUCGUGCCACUGCACUCAAGCCUGGGUGACAGAGCGAAACUCCGUCUCAAAAAAAAAAGUUUCUUCCUUACAUGUAUGUUUCUAUUAGUUUUCUUCUUGGUCUUUCUCAUUUAGUCUUGUGUUGUCUUUUGACAUUCAUAGUAAACUUUUAUCUGCCUCCA